AUCAUUUGCUUAGGUCUGAUCAAUCUGCUCCACGCAAUUUCUCAGUGAUCCUCUGCAUCUCUGCCUACAAGGGCCUCCCUGACACCCAAGUUCAUAUUGCUCAGAAACAGUGAACUUGAGUUUUUCGUUUUAUCUUGAUCUCUCUCUGACAAAGAAAUCCAGAUGAUGCGAGACCUGAUGAAGACAAUACAUGGAAAAUGACAGUCUUGGAAAUAACUUUGGCUGUCAUCCUGACUCUACUGGGACUUGCCAUCCUGGCUAUUUUGUUAACAAGAUGGGCACGACGUAAGCAAAGUGAAAUGUAUAUCUCCAGAUACAGUUCAGAACAAAGUGCUAGACUUCUGGACUAUGAGGAUGGUAGAGGAUCCCGACAUGCAUAUUCAACACAAAGUGACACUUCAUAUGAUAACCGAGAGAGAUCCAAAAGAGAUUACACACCAUCAACCAACUCUCUAGUGUCUAUGGCAUCUAAGUUCUCCCUGGGACAAACAGAACUCAUUCUUCUUUUGAUGUGUUUUAUUUUAGCACUGUCUCGAUCAAGUAUUGGUAGUAUAAAAUGUUUACAAACAACUGAAGAACCUCCUUCCAGAACUGCAGGAGCCAUGAUGCAAUUCACAGCCCCUAUUCCCGGAGCUACAGGACCUUUCAAGCUCUCUCAAAAAACCAUUGUGCAAACUCUAGGACCUAUUGUACAAUAUCCUGGAUCCAAUGCUGGUCCACCUUCAGCACCCCGCGGUCCACCCAUGGCACCCAUAAUAAUUUCACAGAGAACCGCAAGAAUACCUCAAGUUCACACUAUGGACAGUUCUGGAAAAAUCACACUGACUCCUGUGGUUAUAUUAACAGGUUACAUGGAUGAAGAACUUGCAAAAAAAUCUUGUUCCAAAAUCCAGAUUCUAAAAUGUGGAGGCACUGCAAGGUCUCAGAAUAGCCGAGAAGAAAACAAGGAAGCACUAAAGAAUGACAUCAUAUUUACGAAUUCUGUAGAAUCCUUGAAAUCAGCACACAUAAAGGAGCCAGAAAGAGAAGGAAAAGGCACUGAUUUAGAGAAAGACAAAAUAGGAAUGGAGGUCAAGGUAGACAGUGACGCUGGAAUACCAAAAAGACAGGAAACCCAACUAAAAAUCAGUGAGAUGAGUGUACCACAAGGACAGGGAGCCCAAAUAAAGAAAAGUGUGUCAGAUGUACCAAGAGGACAGGAGUCCCAAGUAAAGAAGAGUGAGUCAGGUGUCCCAAAAGGACAAGAAGCCCAAGUAACGAAGAGUGGGUUGGUUGUACUGAAAGGACAGGAAGCCCAGGUAGAGAAGAGUGAGAUGGGUGUGCCAAGAAGACAGGAAUCCCAAGUAAAGAAGAGUCAGUCUGGUGUCUCAAAGGGACAGGAAGCCCAGGUAAAGCAGAGGGAGUCAGUUGUACUGAAAGGACAGGAAGCCCAGGUAGAGAAGAGUGAGUUGAAGGUACCAAAAGGACAAGAAGGCCAAGUAGAGAAGACUGAGGCAGAUGUGCCAAAGGAACAAGAGGUCCAAGAAAAGAAGAGUGAGGCAGGUGUACUGAAAGGACCAGAAUCCCAAGUAAAGAACACUGAGGUGAGUGUACCAGAAACACUGGAAUCCCAAGUAAAGAAGAGUGAGUCAGGUGUACUAAAAGGACAGGAAGCCCAAGAAAAGAAGGAGAGUUUUGAGGAUAAAGGAAAUAAUGAUAAAGAAAAGGAGAGAGAUGCAGAGAAAGAUCCAAAUAAAAAAGAAAAAGGUGACAAAAACACAAAAGGUGACAAAGGAAAGGACAAAGUUAAAGGAAAGAGAGAAUCAGAAAUCAAUGGUGAAAAAUCAAAAGGCUCGAAAAGGGCGAAGGCAAAUACAGGAAGGAAGUACAACAAAAAAGUGGAAGAGUAAGGAUAAAUUUUUUAAAGGCCCAUAAGACAAGUGAUUAUUAUGAUUCCCAUACUCCAGAUACAAACCAUAUCCCAGCCAUUGCCUAAACAGAUUACAAUUAUAAAAUCCCUUUCAUCUUCAUAUCACAGUUUCUGCUCUUCAGAAGUUUCACCCUUUUUAAUCUCUCAGCCACAAACCUCAGUUUCCAAAUAUUUGUUUUAUAAGUUAAGACGUAUAUGAUUCCGUCAAGAAAGACUGGAUACUUUCUGAAGUAAAACAUUUUAAUUAAAGAAAUAUAUAGUAA